CCUCAGAAGCAUCUUCUUGAAACCCAUCUCAAUUCUCUCCUCUUGACAACAUGUGUUGCAACUACUACGGCAACUCCUGUGGCUAUGGCUCCGGCUGUGGCUGUGGCUAUGGCUCUGGCUCUGGCUGUGGCUGUGGCUAUGGAACUGGCUAUGGCUGUGGGUAUGGCUGUGGGUUUGGCUCCCAUUAUGGCUGUGGUUAUGGAACUGGCUAUGGCUGUGGAUAUGGCUCUGGCUCUGGCUACUGUGGCUACCGGCCAUUUUGCUUUAGAAGAUGCUAUUCUUCCUGCUAAAACAUCACUGUCGGAGGACCAUUUGCUUCUAAAAUGACACGUCUGAAGAUAAUGCUGAUUCAAGGAUUCGUACUCCAAGAUUUCUAUAUCCAAGAAUUACAUGCUUGACAGAAUCUUCGACCUC